GUUCGCUUCAGGCAAUACUUGGUAGUCAACCGGGUGAGUGUGAUGGUCAGAGGGGUGCUUAACAAUGAUAGUGUGGCUGCAUUAGUUAGAAGUUAAGAACCCUACAGGGAAACUUCCCCCAGAGGCUGAAAAGCAAAUUGAGGCUUGUUGUAAAAGGGGCGUGUGUUUAGUUAUGGGCCCUUCAAUGGGAGGGCCUUGGGGCUUAAGGUGUUCUAGGGAGUUGUAAUCGGUUUGAAAUAAUUUGUUGGCCUGAUCUGCCCUGGAAAUGGGAUAAUUGCCGACCAGCAUGUCAGCUUUUUCCAAAAACGAAGCUCCUUUUUGGAGUUGAUAGAUUAGGGUUAUGUUUCCUGUUAAAAGGUCAUGAAGGGGUGCAGGAAGGGCUGUGUAAGCUGAGGAAGACAGCGGUAAGCACAUCCAGGUCUCCGAAAAAAAGGAACAGUUAGCUUGCCACAAGAGAGAUUGUGUAAGGUUUAUAGAGCGUUCUAGUUUGAGCAGUAAGGAGUGGUUGUAUUGGUGAGGUUGAUGUGAUUAGGGAAUUUAUAUUGAAAGAAACAAGCAAAAAGAGAAAAAAGUUAUUUGGGUAAGAGUAAAGUCCUGGAAAGCUCCUUGAAGCCAUAGGUCCCAUAGAAUAGUGAGGAGCUGAUCAGGAUGUACAGUGGGAGUUUCAUAAGCAUACCACUGAUGGUCUGUAGUAAGGUUGGUUAGGAAGUGAUGAAAGUUUGGGAGACAAAGAGACAUAAGCGGCUUAUGUGCACUCCUCCUCCUUUUCCUCCAGGAUUUGGCACCACAUUAUCCCAGGAGGAAAAGCAGACGCGUGACAGAGUCAGAGAGCAGGCAUAGAGUGCUGUGGCAGUCAGCCAGUGCCCACAUCAACACCAAGGAGAGUCCUGCGGGUGCUGUGCAAGGCCGGGUGCACGCGUUACUUUGGCUAAAAGGAGGUGAGCGGCACUCUGCCCUUCCAGAGCAAGCAUGGAGCAACAGGAUCAGAGCAUGAAGGAAGGGAGGCUGACGCUUGUGCUUGCCCUGGCAACCCUGAUAGCUGCCUUUGGGUCAUCCUUCCAGUAUGGGUACAACGUGGCUGCUGUCAACUCCCCAGCACUGCUCAUGCAACAAUUUUACAAUGAGACUUACUAUGGUAGGACCGGUGAAUUCAUGGAAGACUUCCCCUUGACGUUGCUGUGGUCUGUAACCGUGUCCAUGUUUCCAUUUGGAGGGUUUAUCGGAUCCCUCCUGGUCGGCCCCUUGGUGAAUAAAUUUGGCAGAAAAGGGGCCUUGCUGUUCAACAACAUAUUUUCUAUCGUGCCUGCGAUCUUAAUGGGAUGCAGCAGAGUCGCCACAUCAUUUGAGCUUAUCAUUAUUUCCAGACUUUUGGUGGGAAUAUGUGCAGGUGUAUCUUCCAACGUGGUCCCCAUGUACUUAGGGGAGCUGGCCCCUAAAAACCUGCGGGGGGCUCUCGGGGUGGUGCCCCAGCUCUUCAUCACUGUUGGCAUCCUUGUGGCCCAGAUCUUUGGUCUUCGGAAUCUCCUUGCAAACGUAGAUGGCUGGCCGAUCCUGCUGGGGCUGACCGGGGUCCCCGCGGCGCUGCAGCUCCUUCUGCUGCCCUUCUUCCCCGAGAGCCCCAGGUACCUGCUGAUUCAGAAGAAAGACGAAGCGGCCGCCAAGAAAGCCCUACAGACGCUGCGCGGCUGGGACUCUGUGGACAGGGAGGUGGCCGAGAUCCGGCAGGAGGAUGAGGCAGAGAAGGCCGCGGGCUUCAUCUCCGUGCUGAAGCUGUUCCGGAUGCGCUCGCUGCGCUGGCAGCUGCUGUCCAUCAUCGUCCUCAUGGGCGGCCAGCAGCUGUCGGGCGUCAACGCUAUCUACUACUACGCGGACCAGAUCUACCUGAGCGCCGGCGUGCCGGAGGAGCACGUGCAGUACGUGACGGCCGGCACCGGGGCCGUGAACGUGGUCAUGACCUUCUGCGCCGUGUUCGUGGUGGAGCUCCUGGGUCGGAGGCUGCUGCUGCUGCUGGGCUUCUCCAUCUGCCUCAUAGCCUGCUGCGUGCUCACUGCAGCUCUGGCACUGCAGGACACAGUGUCCUGGAUGCCAUACAUCAGCAUCGUCUGUGUCAUCUCCUACGUCAUAGGACAUGCCCUCGGGCCCAGUCCCAUACCCGCGCUGCUCAUCACUGAGAUCUUCCUGCAGUCCUCUCGGCCAUCUGCCUUCAUGGUGGGGGGCAGUGUGCACUGGCUCUCCAACUUCACCGUGGGCUUGAUCUUCCCGUUCAUCCAGGAGGGCCUCGGCCCGUACAGCUUCAUUGUCUUCGCCGUGAUCUGCCUCCUCACCACCAUCUACAUCUUCUUGAUUGUCCCGGAGACCAAGGCCAAGACGUUCAUAGAGAUCAACCAGAUUUUCACCAAGAUGAAUAAGGUGUCUGAAGUGUACCCGGAAAAGGAGGAACUGAAAGAGCUUCCACCUGUCACUUCGGAACAGUGACUCUGGAGAGGAAGCCAGUGGAGCUGGUCUGCCAGGGGCUUCCCACUUUGGCUUAUUUUUCUGACUUCUAGCUGUCUGUGAAUAUCCAGAAAUAAAACAACUCUGAUGUGGAAUGCAGUCCUCAUCUCCAGCCUCCCCACCCCAGUGGGAACUGUGCAAAGGGCUGCCUUGCUGUUCUUGAAGCUGGGCUGUCUCUCUCCAUGUUGGCCUGUCACCAGACCCGAGUCAAUUAAACAGCUGGUCCUCCACUUUGCUGGUUCAGCCUUCGUGUGGCUCCUGGUAACGUGGCUCCACCUUGAUGGGUCAACCUUUGUGUGGCUCCUGGUAACAUAACAACAACAGUUACUAUAGUGGUGAGAUGGAAGGAAUCAAAUUUUGCCAGAGAAACUAACUUGGUGGCCCCGACAGGUCUUCCGGGGCCAUGGGCAUUUGUUUAGAGCCAAAUUCAUCCUCUUACCAGAUCCUUUUCCAGAAAUACCUGUCUAGGAAGGUGUGAUGUCAGAAACAAUGACAUCCAGAAAGCUGAGGAACAGGUUCCUGUGGAGACACUGAGUCAGAAUUCUUCAUCCUAAAUUAUUUUGUUAGUGGAAAAUGGAAUUGCUUCUGUGUAGUCAAUAAAAUGAACCUGAUCACUUUUCAACAAGACGUGCUGCUGUUCUUUGAGCAAGUAGAAGGCAGGAGGAAGUUCCCUGCUCAUUCAGGCAGUGUUUUUUUUGUUUUUAUUUUUGCUUUUUUUUUUUUUUUUAAGACGGAGUCUCGCUCUGUCACCCAGGCUGGAGUGCAGUGGUGCGAUCUCAGCUCACUGCAAACUCCACCUCCCGGGUUCACACCAUUCUCCUGCCUCAGCCUCCUGAGUAGCUGGGACUACAGGCGCCUGCCACCACGCCCGGCUAACUUUUUUGUAUUUUUAGUAGAGACUGGGUUUCACUGUGUUGGCCAGGAUAGUCUCAAUCUCCUGACCUCAUGAUCCGCCCACCUAGGCCCCUCAAAGUGCUGGGAUUACAGGUGUGAGCCACUGCGCCCGGCCACUUCAGGCAGUUUGACUGCACGAGUGUCAGUUCCUUGAGGGCAGGGGCUUGGUCAGUUUUGUUUAUGCCUGAAUCCCCAGCAUCUCGAAGAGGGCCUCUGGAGGCUGAGGUGGGAGGAUUGCUUAAGCCUGGGAAGUAGAGGUUGCAGUGAGCUGAAAUUGCACCCUAUACUCCAGCCUGGGCAACACAGUGAGAUCCCAUCUCAAAAAAAAUUUUUUUAAUUGGGCAUGGUGACACGCCUUUGGGGUCCCAGCUAUUUGGGAGGCUGAAAUGGGAGGAUCGCUUGAGCCUGGGAGGUCAAGGCUGCCCUGAGUCAUGAUUGCAUCACUGCACACCAGCCUGCAUGACAGAAUGAGACCUUGUCUCAAAUAAAUAAAUACAUGUAAGAUUGAGGAAGCUUCCAAAUGUCCUCACAUAUGUAAUGAAAUCUUGAGGAGUCUUAAAAUCUUGAGACUGUGGUGGGGGAGGAAGGGAAAAGGAACAGGGUCUUGAUAUGGUUUGGCUGUGUCCCCACCCAAAUCUCAUCUUGAAUUGUAGCUCCCAUAAUUCCCAUGUGUUCUGGGAGGGACCCUGUGGGAGAUAAUUGAAUCAUGGGGGCAAUUUCCCCCAUACUGUUCUCAUGGUAGUGAAUCAGCCUCAUGAGAUCUGAUGGUUCUGUAAGGGGUAAAACCUUUUGCUUGGUUCUCAUUCUCUCUUGCCUGCCACCAGGUAAGACGUGCCUUUUGCUUUCUGGCAUGAUUGUGAGGCCUCCCCAGCCAUGUGGAAUGGCGAGUCCAUUAAAUCUCUUUUUCUUUGCAAUUUACCCAGUCUCUGAUACAUCUUUAUCAGCAGCAUGAAAAUGGUCUAACACAGGUCUCUCCCCAAAAAUAUAGAGAGCUGGAGGUUUUUCUUAGAGAUAUGAAUAAAGGGUGUGAGUGUGAGUGUAUGUGCAAAAAUAUGGAUAAAACCUUGAAAGUGCUGAAUGGCCUGUAGCAAGAAGUGAUGUCUUCUCAUAGAUGGGUGGCAGAGGCUGGUGGCCGGGAGAGAGAGCAGUGGGACUUGGGAGCACUUUUUGUGGGUAUGUAAUGGAGAUUCCACCAGCAACAAGCUAAACCACUCACAAGCGGGCCCAGAGGAAGUAAACAGAACACUGUGGUUGAACCAUCCUUGGCCUUCUGCAGCAAGGAUCUGCAGCCUGGAAGGGGCACAGAAACAACCAAAGAUGAAGGCUCUCAGAGCUGAGGAGAGGCCAGGUCAGAAUAUCAGAAGUCAAGAAACUGCAGCACCUCUAACACAGGGGAGGCUAUGAAGUUCAUGGUUCUGGAUGUCUGCUCCCUGGGUUCAAACCUUGGUCCUGCCACAUUAGUUGUGCAACUUGGAAAGUUACUUGGCUUUUUUGUAUCUCAGUCUUCUCUUCUGUUAAAUGGCACUAAUAGUAAAUGUCUCACAUGUCCAUUGUGAGAAUUAAAUGAC